CUCUCCUGCCUUCCCUGAAUAAACUUACACAAUUUAGUGCUGGGACAUUUGGACCUUUUCUGAAAAUUUGAGUCAGGGAGAGCAUCUUGGGGAGGUGGGAAGGAAGGUAGAAGGAGCAAAGCAACACCCCCCUGAAGCCUGGGAAUAUUGUCAGAACCUUAAAUAUAAUUCAGCUCACCAUUCUGGGUAAGGACAGACUCUACCAAUGAAAAUGGGUGAUUACCAGCUGUGAAACACAAAAACAUACUUUUACGGUUACACAUUCCUUUACAAACAACCGUGUACAUUUCAGCCUCCUGCCCCACCAUUUCUUUUCUCCAGGAGGGAAGGCUGCAUGUCGAGGUGGUCAUAGAAUGUUGAGUAUCAUACUUUCCUACCUCGCUUUUAUUUGCGCGGGUUUAAAUGCGCCUUAACAGAACCCGUGCAAAGGCUUGCCAACUGUCUGGCUGCACCGGAUGAGUAGAGCAUCUUCCUUGGUGGCAGGUGGGUGCGAGGAGGAGGGGCCUGGGCUUUUCUCCGGACAGUGUUUGCCCAGAAGACCAUCAUCCCUGGACUACGUUAGGAGUAAGUGGCACCGCUCCGAGGUGGGGGAAGAAGGGUUAUAAAGGGGGGAGUCCACCACACAUGGUCUUGAAGAAGCUUUUAUAAAAGGCAAAGGCAUCUUUGCCGGACGUUGUUGCAAAGGAGUAGAAACAAGCAGACGAAAACAUCCCAAAGGGUAACCACUAGCAUUGCUGCUUCUUGCAACAUUCAUCCCAGGCUUCCAGCUCAGCCCGCCCCAGGCCAGGUGAUCGGCCGCCACAUCCCCUGCGACUGAAGCACCUGCUCCUCCAUGAACCUGCCAAGAGCUGAGCGCCCUCGCUCCACACCGCAGCGCAGCCUCCGGGACUCCGAUGGGGAAGACGGUAAAAUCGAUGUCCUGGGAGAGGAGGAAGAUGAAGACGAGGUGGAAGACGAGGAGGAGGAGGCGAGACAGCAGUUCCUAGAGCAGUCACUCCAGCCGGGGCUGCAGGUGGCCCGGUGGGGCGGGGUUGCGCUUCCCCGAGAGCACAUCGAGGGCGGCGGCGGCCCGAGUGACCCCUCAGAGUUUGGCACCAAGUUCAGGGCACCGCCAAGGUCUGCGGCGGCCUCUGAAGAUGCCCGGCAGCCGGCAAAGCCCCCCUACUCGUACAUCGCGCUCAUCACCAUGGCCAUCCUGCAAAACCCGCACAAGCGCCUCACGCUCAGCGGCAUCUGCGCCUUCAUUAGUGGCCGCUUCCCAUACUACCGCCGCAAGUUCCCCGCCUGGCAGAACAGCAUCCGCCACAACCUCUCGCUGAACGACUGCUUCGUUAAGAUCCCCCGCGAGCCGGGCCACCCAGGCAAGGGCAACUACUGGAGCCUGGACCCCGCCUCCCAGGACAUGUUCGACAAUGGCAGCUUUCUCCGGCGUAGGAAGCGUUUCAAGCGCCACCAACUGACCCCGGGAGCCCACCUGCCCCACCCCUUCCCUCUACCUGCUGCGCACGCCGCCCUGCACAACCCCCACCCAGGCCCUCUGCUUGGGGCCCCUGCCCCGCCGCAGCCAGUCCCGGGGGCCUACCCCAACACCGCCCCCGGGAGAUGCCCUUACGCUCUGCUGCACCCGCAUCCUCUUCGCUACCUACUGCUCUCGGCCCCCGUCUAUGCCGGGGCACCGAAGAAAGCAGAAGGCGCGGACCUGGCGACCCCGGCACCCUUCCCGUGCUGCAGCCCUCACUUGGUCCUCAGCCUUGGGAGGAGGGCAAGGGUCUGGCGUCGCCACCGGGAGGCGGAUGCAUCUCUUUCAGCAUUGAGAGUAUUAUGCAAGGGGUCAGGGGAGCGGGUACAGGGGCUGCGCAGAGUUUGUCCCCGACCGCGUGGAGCUACUGCCACCUGCUCCAGCGACCAUCAAGCCUGUUGCAUCCCCAAACCGCUGCCCCUUUGCUGCAAGUGUCCGCCGCCGCUGCUGCUCGGACAAUUUUGCAGCAAUAGCAGCAGCAUCAGGAGGACUGCGCCAACGGCUGCGCUCCCACCAAGGGCGCGGUGCUGGGCGGGCACCUGUCGGCCUCGUCGGCGCUGCUGAGGUAUCAGGCAGUGGCGGAGGGCUCUAGGCUGACAUCGCUGGCUGCCCCUUUGGGCGGAGAGGGGACCUCACCAGUUUUUUUAGUAUCGCCCACGCCCAGUUCCCUGGCCAACUCCGCAGGGCCCUCCUAGAGCCAGGUGGGAGUGGGGAGCGACCCGCAGCUGCUCACUCCACCUUGCGCGGCCCAUACUGGGCGUGUGCAUCUGAAUCCCGCUGGAGAGCAAACACGAACUUCUGUUCGUUCGCUGCAAAAUGGUUAGAAAGAUUACAUUCCUCUAAGCUGGAUUACGUUCCUCUAAAAACCACCUGAACGUAACCUUCGCAGGGCGUCAAGUCAUCUUUUCUUGCCUUCGGUUGUGGCUUCUAUGGCUGUCCCGAUUUGCACAUUGUCAUCUUUGAAGGUUAGUGACAUAGCAUUCAUCUUCUGUUGUCACCUUUUCCGUCAUUCCCUGUAUGCCUGAUGGACAGGUUUCACUGAAGUUCAGAGAACAGCAUGCAAAAUUAGCUACCAAUUAAUCUUUAUGAAGUGAGCUGCAUUUCUAGCCACACUGAGCUUAUGUUUUAGCAGGAAGCAUUUUUGGGAAAUGUUUAUGUUAGAGUUUGCCCUUCUUGACAAGGUGAGACAUAAAUGUCUACUUUAGAGACAUGAAUUAAGAUGGGAAGAUAUUUGGGGGAAUCAUUUACUCAAACGCUAAGUAAUAAAGGUACACAAAGGGCAAAUUAUACUAGAUUUCUUUCCCACUUGUUUUCUAUGUCUCUUGCAAUUCACCUUGAUUCCCUUCAGUUUCUGUUUAAUGUAGAAAGUGGCAUUUUCAUUAUUUUAAGCUUCUAGCACAAUGAAAGAAUUUCUCUUUUUCAUGAACAGGAUCAUAAAUGGAAGGGAGGAAGAGUGUCCUAUAUCAUAUUUAUUGUUCAACAAAACACUGCUCCACGGCUUCAAUUCAGUUUAAAAAAGAGAAUUUAUUGAAUAUCUAACACAUACAUAAAAGGCAGUAAAGACAAAUGAGAAGAGGGGAGGAUAUUGAA